GAGCGCCGCCGGGCACUGAGCAGAGCUCCAGGCGCCGAAAGGAAGCUGCAGAGCCCGGCCCGGGGGCGAUUGGCCCGCAGCGCCCCCGGGUCUGUCCCCGGGGCGCCAUGGCCCUACCGCGGCCGGGCGCACCCGCGGGGCCCUGGGCUCGCUGGCUUGCGCGCAGCUGAGCGGGGUGUAGGUUGGAAGGGCCAGGGCCCCCUGGGGCGCAAGUGGGGGCCGGCGCCAUGGAACCCCCGACCGUCCCCUCGGAAAGGAGCCUGUCUCUGUCACUGCCCGGGCCCCGGGAGGGCCAGGCCACCCUGAAGCCUCCCCCGCAGCACCUGUGGCGGCAGCCUCGGACCCCCAUCCGUAUCCAGCAGCGCGGCUACUCCGACAGCGCGGAGCGCGCCGAGCGGGAGCGGCAGCCGCACCGGCCCAUAGAGCGCGCCGAUGCCAUGGACACCAGCGACCGGCCCGGCCUGCGCACGACCCGCAUGUCCUGGCCCUCGUCCUUCCAUGGCACUGGCACCGGCAGCGGCGGCGCGGGCGGAGGCAGCAGCAGGCGCUUCGAGGCAGAGAAUGGGCCGACACCAUCUCCUGGCCGCAGCCCCCUGGACUCGCAGGCGAGCCCAGGACUCGUGCUGCACGCCGGGGCGGCCACCAGCCAGCGCCGGGAGUCCUUCCUGUACCGCUCAGACAGCGACUAUGACAUGUCACCCAAGACCAUGUCCCGGAACUCAUCGGUCACCAGCGAGGCGCACGCUGAAGACCUCAUCGUAACACCAUUUGCUCAGGUGCUGGCCAGCCUCCGGAGCGUCCGUAGCAACUUCUCACUCCUGACCAAUGUGCCCGUUCCCAGUAACAAGCGGUCCCCGCUGGGCGGCCCCACCCCUGUCUGCAAGGCCACGCUGUCAGAAGAAACGUGUCAGCAGUUGGCCCGGGAGACUCUGGAGGAGCUGGACUGGUGUCUGGAGCAGCUGGAGACCAUGCAGACCUAUCGCUCUGUCAGCGAGAUGGCCUCGCACAAGUUCAAAAGGAUGUUGAACCGUGAGCUCACACACCUGUCAGAAAUGAGCAGGUCCGGAAACCAGGUCUCAGAGUACAUUUCCACAACAUUCCUGGACAAACAGAAUGAAGUGGAGAUCCCAUCACCCACGAUGAAGGAACGAGAAAAACAGCAAGCGCCGCGACCAAGACCCUCCCAGCCGCCCCCGCCCCCUGUACCACACUUACAGCCCAUGUCCCAAAUCACAGGGUUGAAAAAGUUGAUGCAUAGUAACAGCCUGAACAACUCUAACAUUCCCCGAUUUGGGGUGAAGACCGAUCAAGAAGAGCUCCUGGCCCAAGAACUGGAGAACCUGAACAAGUGGGGCCUGAACAUCUUUUGCGUGUCGGAUUACGCUGGAGGCCGCUCACUCACCUGCAUCAUGUACAUGAUAUUCCAGGAGCGGGACCUGCUGAAGAAAUUCCGCAUCCCUGUGGACACGAUGGUGACAUACAUGCUGACGCUGGAGGAUCACUACCACGCUGACGUGGCCUACCAUAACAGCCUGCACGCAGCUGACGUGCUGCAGUCCACCCACGUACUGCUGGCCACGCCUGCACUAGAUGCAGUGUUCACGGACCUGGAGAUUCUCGCCGCCCUCUUCGCGGCUGCCAUCCACGAUGUGGAUCACCCUGGGGUCUCCAACCAGUUCCUCAUCAACACCAAUUCGGAGCUGGCGCUCAUGUACAACGAUGAGUCGGUGCUCGAGAAUCACCACCUGGCCGUGGGCUUCAAGCUGCUGCAGGAGGACAACUGCGACAUCUUCCAGAACCUCAGCAAGCGCCAGCGGCAGAGCCUACGCAAGAUGGUCAUCGACAUGGUGCUGGCCACGGACAUGUCCAAGCACAUGACCCUCCUGGCUGACCUGAAGACCAUGGUGGAGACCAAGAAAGUGACCAGCUCAGGGGUCCUCCUGCUAGAUAACUACUCCGACCGCAUCCAGGUCCUCCGGAACAUGGUGCACUGUGCCGACCUCAGCAACCCCACCAAGCCGCUGGAGCUGUACCGCCAGUGGACAGACCGCAUCAUGGCCGAGUUCUUCCAGCAGGGUGACCGAGAGCGCGAGCGUGGCAUGGAAAUCAGCCCCAUGUGUGACAAGCACACUGCCUCCGUGGAGAAGUCUCAGGUACAGGCUCGGGGCAUUGAUGGACGGGCACAGGGUGGGUUUUAUUGACUACAUUGUGCACCCAUUGUGGGAGACCUGGGCGGACCUUGUCCACCCAGAUGCCCAGGAGAUCUUGGACACUUUGGAGGACAACCGGGACUGGUACUACAGCGCCAUCCGGCAGAGCCCAUCUCCGCCACCCGAGGAGGAGUCAAGGGGGCCAGGCCACCCACCCCUGCCUGACAAGUUCCAGUUUGAGCUGACGCUGGAGGAGGAAGAGGAGGAAGAAAUAUCAAUGGCCCAGAUACCGUGCACAGCCCAAGAGGCAUUGACUGCGCAGGGAUUGUCAGGAGUCGAGGAAGCUCUGGAUGCAACCAUAGCCUGGGAGGCAUCCCCGGCCCAGGAGUCGUUGGAAGUUAUGGCACAGGAAGCAUCCCUGGAGGCCGAGCUGGAGGCAGUGUAUUUGACACAGCAGGCACAGUCCACAGGCAGUGCACCUGUGGCUCCGGAUGAGUUCUCGUCCCGGGAGGAAUUCGUGGUUGCUGUAAGCCACAGCAGCCCCUCUGCCCUGGCUCUUCAAAGCCCCCUUCUCCCUGCUUGGAGGACCCUGUCUGUUUCAGAGCAUGCCCCGGGCCUCCCGGGCCUCCCCUCCACGGCGGCCGAGGUGGAGGCCCAACGAGAGCACCAGGCUGCCAAGAGGGCUUGCAGUGCCUGCGCAGGGACAUUUGGGGAGGACACAUCCGCACUCCCAGCUCCUGGUGGCGGGGGGUCAGGUGGAGACCCUACCUGAUCCCCAGACCUCUGUCCCUGUUCCCCUCCACUCCUCCCCUCACUCCCCUGCUCCCCCGACCACCUCCUCCUCUGCCUCAAAGACUCUUGUCCUCUUGUCCCUCCUGAGAAAAAAGAAAACGAAAAGUGGGGUUUUUUUCUGUUUUCUUUUUUUCCCCUUUCCCCCUGCCCCCACCCACGGGGCCUUUUUUUGGAGGUGGGGGCUGGGGAAUGAGGGGCUGAGGUCCCGGAAGGGAUUUUAUUUUUUUGAAUUUUAAUUGUAACAUUUUUAGAAAAAGAACAAAAAAAGAAAAAAAAAAGAAAGAAACACAGCAACUGUAGAUGCUCCUGUUCCUGGUUCCCGCUUUCCACUUCCAAAUCCCUCCCCUCACCUUCCCCCACUGCCCCCCAAGUUCCAGGCUCAGUCUUCCAGCCGCCUGGGGAGUCUCUACCUGGGCCCAAGCAGGUGUGGGGCCUCCUUCUGGGCUUUUCUUCUGAAUUUAGAGGAUUUCUAGAACGUGGUCAGGAAUAGCCAUUCUAGGCGGGGCUGGGGCCAGGGUGGGGGGCAGUCACUGUGGGAGGUCCCAGCUCCAGCCCCCCUCUGGUUUGCUGCCUCCUCUCCCCUCUAAAAAAGUCUUCCGCUUGAUUUUGCACAAUCCCGGCGAUACUCCUGGCGAUACUGACUAGAAAGUCAGGGAGCUGGGGGAGCUGUUCACUUUAGGAUACGGGGGUGGUAUGGAAGGGAGCGUUCACACCGCCAGCCUCGGGCCUGGGAUUUGAGGAGGGCCCUAGACCUCCUCCACUCUCCAUCCCCUUUCCCUUCCACUUUGGGUUCACUUUGAAUUUUCUCCGUUUUUUGGGGCAGUGGCUCUGAUCCACUCACCCCCCCGCCCCCCGCCCCACUUCUAGCUGCUUCUCCUCUUGUUUCUGCCUUAAUAAUUCCCACGGCCACAGGCAAGGGGGUUGCAGUGGCCGCCUGCACCUUGGAUGAGGCAGGGCCAGGCGCCCAGAACCCCCAUCCUGGCCGCACCCCCCUUUCCAGGGUCCUCCGGACCCCACCUUCCACACUCUGAUCACAGCCCCCCUACCUUUUGCCCUAGGAGGAAGCAAUAAUGGUGUAUACCCUCAUUCUCAUUCCUGGGCAGCCCUUCCUUCCACCCUGGCACCAAAAUAAUUUCUCCUCCAUCCGUACCUUGCCUAGCCUCUCCCUCUCCCCCAGCUAGUCCCUGAGCAAUACGGCAGACAGAUGCAAGACCAUUUUUCUCCAAGCCAUGGGGGACUGUUUGGAAGGAAAGCCCCCUCUCUCCCUCCUCCCCUCGCCCUCGGCCUGGUUCUGCAGCUGGACCGACCUCAUUCAUCGCCUGCCCCCUACCCAAUUCUGAGCACACGGUACUGUAGCCCCCAGUUCCUCCCUAGCCUUCCAUCCCUCUGUCCACCCCAGGGGGAGGUAACCCCGCACUCACACUCCCUUGAUGCUGUCUGUACAGGGUUCAUAUUUUGUAGCGAAAGUCGUUUUUGUCCCAGCCGGCGAUCGGAGUGGGCCUUUUCUUUCUUUUUGUUCAUUCUUUACCUUUUUUUCUUUUCUUUCUUUCUUUUUUGUACAUACUGUAAGGUUGGUUUGUAAAUUAUUCUACGGAGGCAAAAAGGGAAAAUAAAAACUUGCCCUUCCCUGGCUGACCCAGUCGGGAAGGUAGGGAAGGAGGUCUCCCGUUGGGAGAGUCUCUGUUCCUGCUGUAUUAUACAAACUGUACCAUAGUCCUGGGAAAAGGGUGGACUCACCGCUGUUGUUUUAUGGGAAGUCGUGUCAUCCUAGGGGUUGGGGCUGGGCAGAGCCUGUCCCCUCCCCCCUUCUCCAGGAGCCAGGGGGUGACUGGAGAGACAGACCCACCCCCAAGCAGGGCUCCUCUCCCCAGGGUGAGCACAGGACCUCUGUAAGCUGCUUGUGUAUUGUCCACUUUGACGAUCAGUCAUUCGGUCCGUUGAUCAAUAAUCCUUCGAUCUUGUCUCCAAUUAAACCGAGGCUUUCACCGAU